AAUUUCCGUUAGGUGCUGAAGGCUGUGGCGCGCGGCUGUCCCCAUUCCCACGUGAAGCGCUACGCUAGCAUCGCUCGGCUGGCGGCUCCCAGCUCGCCGCGGAGCAGUCCCGGCAGCAGCGGGGGACCGGAAGUGGCUCGCGGAGGCUCAGAAGCUAGUCCCGGAGCCCGGCGUGUGGCGCCUCGGAGCACGGUGACGGCGCCAUGUCCCUAAUCUGCUCCAUCUCUAACGAAGUGCCGGAGCACCCAUGUGUAUCCCCUGUCUCUAAUCAUGUUUAUGAGCGGCGGCUCAUCGAGAAGUACAUUGCGGAGAAUGGUACCGACCCCAUCAACAACCAGCCUCUCUCCGAGGAGCAGCUCAUCGACAUCAAAGUUGCUCACCCAAUCCGGCCCAAGCCUCCCUCAGCCACCAGCAUCCCGGCCAUUCUGAAAGCUUUGCAGGAUGAGUGGGAUGCAGUCAUGCUGCACAGCUUCACUCUGCGCCAGCAGCUGCAGACAACCCGCCAAGAGCUGUCACACGCUCUGUACCAGCACGAUGCCGCCUGCCGUGUCAUUGCCCGUCUCACCAAGGAAGUCACUGCUGCCCGAGAAGCUCUGGCUACCCUGAAACCACAGGCUGGCCUCAUUGUGCCCCAGGCUGUGCCAAGUUCCCAACCAAGUGUUGUGGGUGCGGGUGAGCCAAUGGAUUUGGGUGAGCUGGUGGGAAUGACCCCAGAGAUUAUUCAGAAGCUUCAAGACAAAGCCACUGUGCUAACCACGGAGCGCAAGAAGAGAGGGAAGACUGUGCCUGAGGAGCUGGUGAAGCCAGAAGAGCUCAGCAAAUACCGGCAGGUGGCAUCCCACGUGGGGUUGCACAGUGCCAGCAUUCCUGGGAUCCUGGCCCUGGACCUCUGCCCGUCCGACACCAACAAGAUCCUCACUGGUGGGGCGGAUAAAAAUGUCGUUGUGUUUGACAAAAGUUCUGAACAAAUCCUGGCUACCCUCAAAGGCCAUACCAAGAAGGUCACCAGCGUGGUGUUUCACCCUUCCCAGGACCUGGUGUUUUCUGCUUCCCCCGAUGCCACUAUCAGGAUUUGGUCGGUCCCCAAUGCCUCUUGUGUACAGGUGGUUCGGGCCCAUGAGAGUGCUGUGACAGGCCUCAGCCUUCAUGCCACUGGCGACUAUCUCCUGAGCUCCUCCGAUGAUCAGUACUGGGCUUUCUCUGACAUCCAGACAGGGCGUGUGCUCACCAAGGUGACAGAUGAGACCUCCGGCUGCUCUCUCACCUGUGCACAGUUCCACCCUGACGGACUCAUCUUUGGAACAGGAACCAUGGACUCUCAGAUCAAGAUCUGGGACUUGAAGGAACGUACUAAUGUGGCCAACUUCCCUGGCCACUCGGGCCCCAUCACUAGCAUCGCCUUCUCUGAGAAUGGUUACUACCUGGCUACAGCGGCUGAUGACUCCUCUGUCAAGCUCUGGGAUCUGCGCAAGCUUAAGAACUUUAAGACUUUGCAGCUGGAUAACAACUUUGAGGUAAAGUCACUGAUCUUUGACCAGAGUGGUACCUACCUGGCUCUUGGGGGCACGGAUGUCCAGAUCUACAUCUGCAAACAAUGGACGGAGAUUCUUCACUUUACAGAGCAUAGCGGCCUGACCACAGGGGUGGCCUUCGGGCAUCACGCCAAGUUCAUCGCUUCAACAGGCAUGGACAGAAGCCUCAAGUUCUACAGCCUGUAGGCCCUGGCCCUUCUGAUGGAAGCUGGGCCUCAUCUCAGUAGAGGGGUAGAAUUAGGGUUUGGGGGGGGGGGUGGGGGGAAUCUAUGGGGGGAGGGGGCUCUGUGGGGUGGGACAUUCACAUCAUUUCACUCUGGUCUGAGUGGUGGCCUGAGAACCAUGGUGGCAUGGACCACCCUCAUCCAUGCAACUCCAGGCCCCAUGGGAACGGAUGUGGAAGGAAGAACUGUCACCCUCUUAAGGCCCAGGGUCGGAGCCCAGGGCCUCUCCCUUCCUGUCGUUCAAUGGACGUGGUGGUGGCUGUUCCACACCCAUUUUGUUGCAGUUCCUGUGAGACAGGAGAGGCUGAGCCAAGGGAACUGUGAAGGGGAUGGGCAGGAGGGCUUGUGCAGGGUUUUGUAAGCAGUGAUCUAGUUUCAUUAAAAAAAGAAAACAAUAACCAUAACCACCUCCCCGUGUCUGUCUGCACCAGGAGCACCUGGGACUGGGAAGGUCAAGGGGAGGGAGCACACACUGGGACACUGGCUUCCGGGAAGCCCAUCUUCCUUUCCUUUCACAGCUCUUACCCUUUUUUUUUUUUUUUAAUUGCACAGCAGAAAUAAAAACAAAUCUGCAGAUGAAA